AGUCGCCAGCGGAUCCCGCGCGCUGGAGAAGUGCAGUUCCCCCUGGUUACCAACUCGCCCGCUUUUCCUUCGGACUAAGGGAGCCGUCGAAGAGCGCUCGCCAAAGGCGCAGCCGUUUCUCCCUACGGUGCCGCCGCUCCUCCUGCAGCCGCCCGUAGGUAGCGGGCCGUUUUCCUCACCUGUCCCUGACAGGCGCCCUCAGGGAGCCGCGGUCCGCGAUGUCAAGCGAGGAAAGCUACCGGGCCAUCCUGCGUUACCUGACGAACGAGCGCGAGCCGUAUGCGCCGGGCACCGAGGGCAAUGUCAAGCGUAAAAUCCGAAAAGCUGCCGCCUGCUACGUGGUGCGCGGCGGGACUCUGUAUUACCAGCGGCGGCAGCGGCACCGCAAGACCUUCGCGGAGCUGGAGGUGGUGCUGCAGCCGGAGCGACGCCGGGACCUCAUCGAGGCGGCGCACCUGGGUCCCGGCGGCACUCACCACACCCGGCAUCAGACCUGGCACUACUUGUCCAAGACGUACUGGUGGCGAGGUAUAUUGAAGCAAGUCAAAGAUUACAUUAAACAGUGUAGCAAAUGCCAGGAGAAACUAGAUCGAUCCCGUCCAAUAUCAGAUGUUUCAGAAAUGUUGGAAGAAUUGGGACUAGACCUUGAAUCUGGAGAAGAAAGUAAUGAAUCGGAAGAUGACCUGAGCAACUUUACUUCAUCUCCAACUACAGCAUCCAAGCCUGCAAAAAAGAAGCCAGUAUCCAAACAUGAACUUGUGUUUGUUGACACCAAAGGAGUGGUAAAACGUUCUUCUCCAAAACAUUGUCAGGCUGUCUUAAAACAGCUGAACGAACAGAGACUUUCCAACCAGUUCUGUGAUGUUACUUUGUUAAUUGAAGGAGAAGAGUACAAAGCUCAUAAAUCUGUUUUGUCAGCAAAUAGCGAGUAUUUUCGAGAUCUUUUUAUUGAGAAAGGAGCUGUUUCCAGUCAUGAGGCUGUGGUGGAUCUUUCUGGUUUUUGUAAGGCCAGCUUCCUUCCUUUACUGGAAUUUGCCUAUACUUCUGUACUAAGUUUUGAUUUCUGUAGCAUGGCUGAUGUAGCCAUCUUAGCUCGUCAUCUUUUCAUGUCAGAAGUCUUAGAGAUUUGUGAAAGUGUACAUAAGCUAAUGGAAGAGAAGCAGCUAACAGUAUAUAAGAAGGGCGAAGUACAAACAGUUGCAUCCACCCAGGACUUACGAGUACAGAAUGGAGGUACAGCACCUCCUGUUGCUAGCAGUGAGGGAACCACAACAAGUUUACCUACUGAACUUGGGGAUUGUGAAAUUGUACUACUGGUAAAUGGAGAAUUGCCAGAAGCUGAGCAGAAUGGAGAGGUAGGACGACAGCCUGAGCCCCAGGUUUCUUCAGAGGCUGAAUCUGCCCUGUCAUCAGUAGGAUGUAUAGCUGAUUCCCAUCCUGAAAUGGAGUCUGUUGAUUUAAUAACAAAAAACAACCAGACAGAACUAGAAACUUCAAACAACAGAGAAAAUAACACAGUUUCUAAUAUACACCCUAAACUUUCAAAAGAGAAUGUAAUUAGUAGCUCGCCAGAGGAUAGUGGUAUGGGAAAUGAUAUAUCAGCUGAGGAUAUUUGUGCCGAAGACAUUCCAAAACAUAGGCAGAAAGUUGACCAACCUUUAAAAGAUCAGGAAAAUCUAGUUGCAUCAACAGCAAAGACAGACUUUGGCCCUGAUGAUGAUACUUAUAGAAGCAGGCUUCGACAACGUUCUGUUAAUGAAGGGGCAUAUAUUCGACUACACAAGGGAAUGGAGAAAAAGCUGCAGAAACGGAAAGCCGUUCCCAAGUCAGCAGUUCAACAGGUGGCUCAGAAGUUAGUUCAAAGAGGAAAAAAGAUGAAACAGCCAAAAAGAGAUGCUAAAGAGAACACAGAAGAAGCAUCUCAUAAAUGUGGGGAAUGUGGAAUGGUUUUUCAGAGACGAUACGCCCUUAUAAUGCACAAACUGAAACAUGAAAGAGCUAGAGAUUACAAAUGUCCAUUGUGUAAAAAACAGUUUCAGUACAGUGCCUCUUUGCGAGCACAUCUUAUUCGUCAUACCAGAAAAGAUGCACCCUCUUCAUCCUCGUCCAAUUCCACGUCUAAUGAAGCAUCGGGAACAUCAUCUGAGAAGGGCAGAACCAAGCGGGAAUUUAUAUGUUCCAUAUGUGGAAGAACAUUACCUAAAUUAUAUUCUCUCCGAAUACAUAUGUUAAAGCACACAGGUGUAAAGCCACAUGCAUGCCAGGUCUGUGGAAAGACUUUUAUCUAUAAGCAUGGUCUAAAAUUACAUCAGAGUCUUCAUCAAUCACAGAAGCAGUUCCAGUGUGAACUGUGUGUUAAGUCAUUUGUUACCAAACGGAGUCUUCAAGAACAUAUGAGUAUUCACACAGGAGAGUCCAAGUACCUUUGCUCAGUUUGUGGAAAGUCUUUUCAUAGGGGCUCUGGACUCAGCAAGCACUUCAAGAAACACCAACCAAAGCCUGAGGUUCGAGGCUAUCAUUGUACUCAAUGUGAAAAAAGUUUCUUUGAAGCUAGAGAUCUUCGCCAGCACAUGAACAAACAUCUUGGUGUGAAGCCAUUCCAGUGCCAAUUUUGUGAUAAGUGCUAUAGUUGGAAGAAAGAUUGGUAUUCCCAUGUGAAGUCUCAUUCUGUCACUGAGCCUUAUAGGUGUAAUAUAUGUGGCAAAGAAUUUUAUGAAAAAGCUUUGUUCAGAAGGCAUGUAAAGAAAGCUACCCAUGGGAAGAAAGGAAGAGCAAAGCAAAACCUGGAACGGGUGUGUGAAAAAUGUGGAAGAAAAUUCACUCAGCUAAGAGAGUAUAGGAGACACAUGAACAACCAUGAAGGAGUUAAGCCAUUUGAGUGCUUAACAUGUGGAGUAGCUUGGGCUGAUGCCCGAUCUCUAAAACGCCAUGUCAGAACACAUACUGGUGAACGGCCCUAUGUCUGUCCUGUAUGUAGCGAAGCCUACAUAGAUGCUCGAACACUCCGUAAACAUAUGACUAAAUUCCACAGAGACUAUGUGCCUUGCAAAAUUAUGCUGGAAAAAGACACCCUUCAGUUUCAUAACCAAGGAACUCAAGUGGCACAUGCUGUUAGCAUCUUAACAGCAGGCAUGCAGGAACAAGAAAGCAGUGGUCCUCAAGAACUUGAGACUGUGGUAGUGACAGGAGAAACUAUGGAAGCUCUGGAAGCUGUUGCAGCUACUGAAGAGUAUCCAUCGGUAUCUACACUUUCUGACCAAAGUAUUAUGCAAGUGGUUAAUUAUGUAUUAGCACAACAGCAAGGACAGAAGCUAUCUGAAGUUGCAGAAGCUAUUCAAACUGUUAAAGUAGAGGUAGCACAUAUUUCAGGAGGAGAAUGAGUAUGUUAAUGAAGAUAAAAAGAAGUGACAUCUCUUGUACACUGAACUCACAGAACAUUUGUUUACAAUUCUGUGUGACUGUCUGCUUGGAGUUUACAUAUCAAAGUUCUGGGCUGUUUGGUAACGUAACGUUUCCAAACAUUUUGUCUGGCCAAUGGGUUCUAUAGAAAAGUCCGUUUAGUGUAGAGAAAUUGAAAACAGAUCUAUUAGGUUGGUGCAAUUGCUUUUGCACCAACCUAAUAUUUGAUGGCAGUGGUUUAUCAUGAUAUACCUUUUAUGAAUUAAUGUUUAUAAAUGACUGUACUGAAUUUAAAACCGUACAGUUUCAUUUGCAUUUUGACAUUACUUUAUUAUACAUUUUGCAUUUAAAAGGCUGCACCAGUUGGCUUUUCUUCUGUUUUAUUCUCAAAAUAUAGAGAUUCUGUGAUUUAUUUGCCCUGUUUAUGGAUUAAAAAGAAAAUUCUAAUAUAAAGCAUUUCAAUAGGAUGCAUAGGUAUAUUACGUUUUUUAAAUGCUUUAGAUCUGUGAUUCUUGACUUACUAUUUAUUUUAUCCCCUUUUAAGUCAGGGAUGCUUUAUUCUAUUUUAAAGCACUUAUGAGUUACAUGUUGUAAUCAAGUUUGCACAAUAUAUUUAUCUAUAUGAGGAACCCAUAAAUGAAUAGCUAAUUUUUAAAAUGCCAUUAAAAUGCAUGAAAUGCUUAUUAAAACCUUACUAUACUAUUUCUUCAAGGCAAGUAAAUUGACCAUGAGAAAAGAACACAGUUAUUAAACACUGUUGACAGGAAAAUUCUCCUUGAUAACAUAGGACAAUUAAUGGAAAAAAAAAUUCUCAUUAUUUGCAAAGAAUGAACAAGUUAAUGAACAAACAAACUAGAUUUGGUAUGUUUUCAGCUUUUGUAUCAUGUUUAAUUGUUUAAUUUGGUUGAAAAACUGCAGUUGAGAAAUCAGAUAGCAAUAUAGACAUUCACAGCAGCUCUGUGGAUACCAUGUAAUUGUCAGGUAAUUUCAGAAUGUUGAAAAUUAUUCAGUGCAGCCCUCAUAGUAUCAUACUUGAAGAAAUUGAUUACAGUUCCACUAAAUUGUUGAAGAUAAAUUAUUUUUAAAGGUUAUGAAAACUAAGUUAUAUUAAUUCAUAUGUUUGAUUUUUAAAUCCCACCUCCUCAAGCUAUCCAAUUUUCUGACUUUGAAAAUAACCAUGAGAGAUGCCACAUUUCUCUCUGGGAAACUACCACUCAAAGAAUAAUUGUUAAAAAUUAAGCUUUUAGGUAUUAGAAGCUGUUAUAAAGUAUAAAAUUAAGAUAUAAGCAGAUCACAUGUAAAUCAUUCCUAAAGCACAAGAAAAGAAUGUGCCUUGAUGUACAUAUAUUACUAAGUUGCCUCUCCCAGUUUACUUUAAAAAUGGCUUUAAGGAUAAAGAAUAAAUGUGAUAGCUGUGCAUGCAUUAUAUAUUUGCAUUUGCAAAUUUCCCAUUGUUUUAACAGCUGUGUGGCUGACUUUCAAUUUUAAGACGUGAAUUGACAUACAGCCCAUAACUUUAUAAUGGCUGCUCAUUUAUCUUAUCUUUCAGUUAGUGGAAAAACAUUUCAACCUGACUAAAAUUUGGAAUUGUGUCUUUUAUGUUCCAUCCUCUGUUGUUACUAGAUUUAGUUUAAAAAUUGUGUAUGACCAUUAAUGUAUGUCAUAAACAUGUAAAUAAAAGAUGUUGAAUCUUGUUGAAAAGCAUGAACUUUGGAGUUGAGCUUGUUACUAUUUUCAGUUCAUAAAUCAGUUGUUACUUGAUGUGUUAUUAAGUUAAUUUAUUUUUAAAGGGAAAGGAAAUAAAACACUAAAAAAUAACGAUUGGAGGAACACAAUAUUAAAACUUCUUACUCUUACAUAUAAUUGAUAUGGACAAGAGGCAAGGAAAUAAUGGGUAGAAGAGGGCAGUUCCCCAGCAAAAGCCUGGAAACCCAUGGCCCUAAAUGGGAACAGGCAUUCCUGUUUUCAUGCCCAAAUGUUGCCUUUUGGCCCACCACGCCCUCCUAUCCUGUAUCCAUAUAAACCCUAAACCCCAGGCUCCAUGAGCAGAAGAGUGUUGCGGCAGAGGAGAGAAGAGAGGAGCAUCUAAACGUCCAGAGGAGUUCAGCUGGGGACGGUUGGAGAGGAGAUCAUCUUCCCACUCCAUCCCCUUUCCAGCUCCCCAUCCAUCCUGCUGAGAGCCACCUUUAUCCAGCAAUAAAAUCCCCUGCAUUUACCAUCCUUCAAUUUGUCCAUGUGACCUGAUUCUUCCUGGACGC